AGCGCUGCUGUCCCCGCCGUGCGCCCUUCGCCGCUGAGCUCGCAGCCUCCGGCGCCCACCUCCACCUCCAGUGUCCCGCCUCGGGCCGUCGCCCUCCAGCGGCUCGCGAGCGUGGGAGACGUACCUGGGCAGGCACUGUCCAGCCCAGGCCCAGGCACAGCCGUGAGGGGCGAGGCACGGGGACAUCCUGGCGGCCACCAUGGUGGCCACGUGCCUGCAGGUGGUGGGCUUCGUCACGAGCUUCGUGGGCUGGAUCGGGGUCAUCGUGACCACCUCCACCAAUGACUGGGUGGUGACCUGCGGCUACACCAUCCCCACCUGCCGCAAGCUGGAUGAGCUGGGCUCCAAGGGGCUGUGGGCCGACUGCGUCAUGGCCACGGGGCUGUACCACUGCAAGCCCCUGGUGGACAUCCUCAUCCUGCCGGGCUACGUGCAGGCCUGCCGCGCCCUGAUGAUUGCUGCCUCGGUCCUGGGUCUGCCGGCCAUUUUACUGCUGCUGACUGUUCUUCCCUGCAUCCGGAUGGGCCAGGAGCCCGGUGUGGCUAAGUACAGGCGGGCCCAGCUGGCUGGUGUUUUGCUCAUUCUGCUGGCUCUCUGCGCCCUUGUUGCCACCAUCUGGUUCCCUGUGUGCGCCCACCGUGAGACCACCAUCGUGAGCUUUGGCUACUCCCUGUAUGCAGGCUGGAUUGGUGCUGUGCUGUGCCUCGUGGGUGGCUGUGUCAUCCUCUGCUGCGCUGGAGAUGCCCAGGCCUUUGGUGAAAACCGUUUCUACUACACUGCGGGCUCUAGCUCCCCGACUCAUGCGAAGAGUGCCCACGUAUAAGAGGGCUGCCCGGCUGCCCACAGAGGUGCUGUAGAUGCUGGGCCCAGGGCCCUAGGUUUGCUCGUCACAGUGUGGGGAAGCCCAUUCCUCUGCCAGGCUCUAAAGCCAAAGGUCUAGAAAAGCAUCCUGUCUGGCAUUUUGUAGUCUUAACUUCUCCCCAUUUCCCCCAUCUUUUGGUUGCCUUAAAAGAAAUCUCUAGCUCAGAUAAUGCCCAGACAUUUUUUUCCCUUGGUGUUGCCCCUAUUAGCUCUUUUCUUGGGCAUUCUUUUGCUGUUUAUUAAAAAUAUAUUAUAUAUAUUUUGUUUCUUUAAAUUUCAAAUGUUUUGCAAACAUCACUGAGUUAGGUGGGGGUGGGGAAGAGAAAUACAAGAUACUUUUUUUUUUUUUUUUUUUUUUUUUUUUUUAAAUAGGGCCUCACUCUGUUGCUCAGGCUGGAGUGCGGUGGUGUGAUCUCGGCUCAUGUAGCCUCAACCUCCCCGGCUCAAGUGAUCCUCCUGCCUCAGCCUCCCAAGUAGCUGGGACUACAGGCGUUCACUACUACACCCAGCUAAUUUUUAAGUUUUUUAUAGAGAUGAGGGCUCCCUAUGUUGCCCAGGUUGGUCUCGAACUCCUGGACUCAAAGUAUCCUCCCGCCUCGGCCUCCCAAAGUGUUGGGAUUAUAGGAGUGAGCCACCACACCGGCCAAGAUGCUUUUCAAACUGAUACAGAUGACAAUGGGAGCCUCAUAAAGAUGGCUUUUGUUUCUUCCCUUCAAGGUCAUUUACUUGUACGAGACAGAAAAAGAUAGCAUUGGGGACAUGGGAUGGGGGAGGGAGGGCAAUAGUGGAACGAACUUUCCAUGGGAAACUUUCCCUUUUGUAAGUUGAGGGCCAGGGGUAGGGAUAUUUUUUAGUUUGUGAUUUUACAUUUAUCUGUACAUACUUUUUCAAGAUUGAUCAUUUUUAUAACCAUGGUUUUCCUGAAAUCCUCAAUUCAUCAAUAUGAAGGAAAUGAACCACAUAGACUUUAUGCAAUAAAUAACAGUGCAAGUGAGUAUAACUCUAACUGAUGUUCCACAAAACAUUUUUGAUUUCAGGUUUGUAUGAUGUAGUUUUUAAUCGUACAUUUUCAUAUGCUUCAAACUAACACAUUUUUAAAGCUUUCCCCCACUUUUCUCUCUAUUUGUAUUGUUAGCCAUCUUGAAGUGAUGUUGUUUAACAUAAAUUGUACUGUUGAAUUUGGCUUUACGGGUGUAAACACUGAUGGUAUAUCAGUAUCUGAGACCCCAAACUCUCCAAAUACUGAUGGUGCAUUUUAUUCUUGAAGUGAAAUCUGUGCAAUAAAAUAACAGACUGUCUGCAAAACUGGCCUUCAAUCUUCUGUUGUAUCCAGAGGUAUCAUUAUUGAUUUAAAAAAAUCUCAUUAAUCUCUACUGGUAAUUUAUAGGGAAUCUGAUCAGUGAUUCAAGAACAAGUAAUUCUGCAUUGCCUUGAAUAAUUAAAAAGUUAUAUUUUAUUCACGGUAUUGCAGUGGUAAUUUGUGGUCAUGAAAGCAUAACCUCAGUGCUCUCUAGGUUUCUUAAGUGGGGUGACUUUAUGGCAUCUUUAAUCAUCGAUCAAUGGGCAGCAAUCAGAAACAAAGUUCUCAGCAUUAUGCAGUUAAUGUCCUUCAUCUACUUCUAACACUUAGUAAAGGAAUUGAUUGGCUAGGUAUAAAAAGAGAAUUAACGAAACCUAUUUUAUUGGAUCUUUAAGUAAUAAUAUCUAAAUACAUUUCGUUCAAACAUACAUAUGUAGCUGUUUGGACAUUUUGGACAAAGACACAUUGAGUUGAUUUUUAUUUGUUUUUCUGUUCCAGAAACUUCAUCAAGUUACGGGCCUGGUCUAAGAAAACACAUUGCAAUCUAUUUUGGCAGACUUCUUUCAAAUAAAAUACUAAUUUCAUUAGCUGAUAGUA